UGGGUAACAGAGCGGGGGAAAAAAUAAAAUAAAAUUAAGCAAAGCAUAAUUUCCAUCUUUACAAAUCCUGAAUGAAUAUUAGUUCAUGCUUUUAUGUCUUUAGAAAACAUAGUUGGAAUGGUGUCUUAGUCUGUUUGGGCUGCUAUAGCAGAAUACCAUAUACUGGAUAGCUUAUAAACAGAAAUUUAUUUCUCACAGUUCUGGAGACUGGGAAGUUCAUGAUCAAGGUGCUGGCAGAUUUGGUGUCCUUUGAGGCCCGACUUUCUGGAUCAGAGACAGUGCCUUCUAUUUGUUUCCUCAUGUGGUGGAAGGCAAGAGGCACCUAUCUAUGUUCUCUCUUAUGAGGGUGCUAAUCCCAUUUUGAGGGUACCACCCUCAUGACCUAAUGACUUCCCAAGGGCCCCACCUCCUAAUAGCAUUACCUUGGGGGUUAGCAUUUCAGCAUAUGACUAUGAAGGCAAAACAUUUAGACCAGAGCAAAUGGUCUAGGCCAGAUUAUCACACUUGUCCUUUGUAUUCUCUUUGUGGUGUGAGUACUAAGCUAAAAUAGCCUAGAAUAUUAAAAAUCGUCACGUAAUAUAUACGCAUAGUUUAAAAAUGAAAUAGUAUAAAAAGACUUAUGAUGAAAACACAAUAUCCUUCCCCACAAAACAUACUCUGUUCCCUAGAUGUAGCUGCUUUUUAUUCCUUGAGCUGUUUCUUGCUGAUUCUUCAUUUUCGAAAUCUGUUUAUUGCAUUCUCCCCAUUCAUUACCUUUAGCCAUUGUCUGUUGUAUUCUUUUGUGGUAGAAAGGAUUUACCUUUUAUCCUCCUCUGUUUUCCCAAUAAAGUUUAAUGACAAGUUUUAGCUUAAUCAAUAUUCAGUGUGUAUAUUUUAUUUGUCCUUUGGUGUCUAUGGGGGAUUUGUUCCAGGACCUCCUAUGGAUACCAAAACCUGAUGCUCAAGGCCCUGACAUAAAAUGGGAUAAUAUUUGGAUAUAACCUGUGCAUAUCCUCUGUACACUUUAAUCUCUAGAUUACUUACAAUACCUGAUACAAUGUAAAUGAUAUGCAAAUAGUUGUUAUACUGUAUUGUUUAGAGAAUAAUGUCAAAAAAGGCUGUAUUUGUUUAGUAUAGACACAAUUUUCUGUUGAAUAUUUUUGAUCCACAUUUGGUUGAAUUCACAGACAUGGAACCCAGGGAAUGUGGAGCGCUGACUCUCUAUCAUCUAUGUUGUUGUUUCCUGACAAGCAACUAAUAUACAAACAUUUCUUUUCCUUUUUUUGUCAGAAUUUUGUUUUUCCUGGAGUUGGUAAUUGCCUUGUUCUUUUCUUCCCCCUUGGGUUUAAUAUUUUUUAUACCUAUCACAAAUUCUUUCUACACUGUCUAAUGCUCUCAGAACAAUUUUCCACAUGGUUAAGAUUUCAGAUAAUUAAUCAGCUUUUUUUUUUCCCUGACAACUUUCCUCUUUGAGGCCUGUUGGCCUGCUUCAUCCUUUACUAUUUGCCUUCUGGCCUGGCUUCACAGCUGUCAUCAUGGAAUUUGCUCCCAUCCUGGGAAUUUCUCCUCACUCUUUUCUAUAUUCAAUCCCCAGUUAAUUAUAUAAGGGAAAGUCUCAGUUUCUUGGCUAAUUUAUUCAAUUUGAUACAUACAACCCCUACUAAUAUAUGGAAUCCAAGUAGUAGGGAGGUAAUUUUUUUCCCCUUGCAACUUAGCGUGCCUGAAAAUUUCACCAUAUCCUUCUACUUAAUUGUGGGUUUAGCCAGGUAAAGAAUUUUGGGUUGAAAAUAAUUUUUCCCUGGGGUGGGGGAGGGGGGAGGGAUAGCAUUGGGAGAUAUACCUAGGGCUAGAUGACGAGUUAGUGGGUGCAGCGCACCAGCAUGGCACAUGUAUACAUGUGUAACUAACCUGCACAUUGUGCACAUCUACCCUAAAACUUAAAGUAUAAUAAUAAAUAAAUAAAUAAAAUAAAUUUUCCCUAGAAUUUAAAGCUUUACUCUCUUGUCAUAUACCAUCUCAUGGCUUGAAUGAGAAUUCUGACACUAUUCUAAUCGCCUGUGACUUGUUUUUUUCUCUCUGGAAGGUUUUAAGAUAUUUUUAUUUCAAAUGUGAAAUUUCAGAAGCAUAUGCUUUGAGUAUUUUUUCUUUCAGUUACAAAUUGAAUUAGCUCUACUAAUAUGGAACCUUAUGUUUUUUGGUUCUGGACAUUUUCUAGUAUAUUUCUUUGAUUAAAAAUACAUUUUAUAGUCUGUUUUCUUUUUCUGGAAAUUCGGUUAGUUGGUCUUGGAUUUUUUAAAAAGCUAUUUCCUCCUAUAUUUUAUGUAUGUCUUGUUCUUUCUGGGAGAAUUUUUAAAAAUGUUUCAAAUCUUGGAUAAGAUUGUGAUAUUUUUGUUCUCUAAAUGUUUCUCUUUUAAAACUGUCGGCCUGGCGCGGUGUCUCACGCCUGUAAUUCCAGCACUUUGGGAGGCCGAGGUGGGUGGAUCAGCUGCGGUUGGGAGUUUGCGACCAGCCUGCCCAACAUGGAGAAACCCUGUCUCUACUAAAAAUACAAAAUUAGCCGAGUGUGGUGGUGCAUGCCUGUAAUCCCAGCUACUCGGGAGGCUGAGGCAGGACAAUCCCUUGAACCCGGGAGGCGGAGGUUGCAGUGAGCCGAGAUUGUGCCAUGGCACUCCAGCCUGGGCAACAAGAGCGAAACUCUGUCUCAAAAUAAAUAAAUAAAUAAAUAAAUAAAACUGUCAUGCUACUGUUUUUUCUUUUGGGAUGGGUGCAUUACUUUUUCUUAUCUUUCUAAUAUCAAUUGUAAGUUAAAAAAUUAUCCCAUCCUCCAUUCUCUUUCCCCAUUUCCCAGCCUAUCCUUCCUCAUCUUCUCCACCUCCUUUAUCCUCCUUCUCCUCUCUUCUCUUUCCCUUGCUUUCUCCCUCCUGUCCUUUUCGUCCCCCUUCGCCUUCUCCUCCUCCCCAUUCUCUUUCCCACUCCUCCCUCACUCUUCCCCAUCGGCCUCCCUCACUUUCUUCUCUUUGUCAUUUCCUCAUCUCCUUCUCAAUCUCUUCCUUCUGUUAUUUUGUUUUGCUUUUGCUUAUAUUUUGGAUUGAGGCAGUAAAACUGUUUCUGCUUUGGUGUGAUUUGUUGACUGGUCCUCACCAGCAAGGGAAUGACCUCGUAUGCUGAUACAUUUCAUAGUGAAUAACUGCUACAUGGCUGUCUUAUGAUAGUACAGUCCGUAACAGGUAGAGCAUUGCAUCAGCUGUGCACCUGAAUUGGAAUAUGAUGCCCUAGAACUGGACAUGUGGAGAACCCAGGAGCAAUCUUGAACUCGGAGGAAAUAGCUGUCCUUCCUGGUUUUCAUGGUAAUGUAUGGGACUUGAGCAAGUCUAAGUCACUGACACUGAAGCAGUAGUGUAGAUAUGUACUAUUUUAGAAGAUCAUUUACUGAAGAAAGGACAUUUCCUAAAAGAAACAAUAUAUGGGUAUCACUGGUAUUAUACUCCUAGUAUUAUACAACCCCUUUGUGGGUGUUCUGGGCCCUGAACACUAAAUGUCUGUAUCACUACCCCCUUUUCCUCCCGCAUUCUAUAACAACCAUAAAACUACUCCCCACCUCUCCUGCUUCCACUGCCCCAAAACCACCUAUUUCGGAACACCUGUGUGAAGAGUGGGACCUCCCCUGGUGAAGAAAGUGUUCGCCAGCUUACGGGAUUCCCUUUCCCUUUCACCAUCACUGGAGAGCUCCCCUUCCUCCCCUGGCCUGUACCAUCUGGCUCCUUCUAGGCACAGGUGCUAUUUCAAGUGCUCUGAGGCAUUGAAAAAAGAAAACGCGUUUUGGAAUCAGACAUUCAUGAGUAUUCACAGCAUUGUCUCUGCCCAGAAUUCCCUUUCCCCAUGUCCUCAUGUCUACAUUCUACAUUAAAUAAUCAGUUCAAAAGUCUCUACAGUAGUUAUUCUUUGAAUUCCUGUGCUUAAUCAUCUGUGACUCUUCUGUAAUGUUUUAGUCUUGUCGUUUUUAUUACACAACUAUACGUCCUUAGAGGUCAAAGUAGAAGGCUUCCAUUUAUUAAAUGCUUACAGGGUGCUGCUUUGCAUAUUUCAGGGGUAAAACAGAGCUUGAAGGAGAUUGAAGAAUUUGCCCAGAGUUAUGCCACUGGUAAAUGGCAAACCUAGAUUUGAACCUAGACUUUUCUGGUUCCAUAACUUUUAUCUCCUCUCUCUGUGCCUUGUUGCUAAAUAAAUUUGUAUAAAUAAAUAAAGAAAUACAUAAGUAUUUUAGCAUAAAGAUGAAUAAGCAGCCCUGAUGAAAGCAGGCAUGUCUCUUCUUUGCCCUCUGUCAACUUCCAGUUUUGGUGGAGAAAAUAGCAAAACAGACUGCCUGGUCAUGGAUUUCUGCAUAUAACCUGAACUUUAAACAUGCCUGGAACACAUUUGGUUCUGAUUUAAAACAAGUUGGCUUGCACCAUUGCCAUGUUAUUACAAAUACAAAAGAAAUAUAAACUUCAUUCCAUUAAAUAACCAUCCACAUAAACUCUUAAAUACUUUCAUGGCUUUGGGCUGGGCCAAAGCUGGAUAUUAAGGAAAUGAUUAUUAAUGUUACAUAUUUUAUUCAAACUGCUCUAAUUCUUUUAACCUUCCCUCCAUCCCUAAAAGUACCAGUCAACCUUUUCCUUCCUCCUGCAAAAUGUUCCCAGGAGGUUAAAACAGAUAGAACUUUGAUUUCAAGCUACUGACUCUUACUAUUUGGAAAUACUCUUUGUUUUCAGUUCCUCAUAGCCUGUAGCUGUGUGCUCUACUUGAAACUUUUCAAUCCUCCUUGGAUGACAGCAAAGUUAGUUAUUAUUCCCUAUAGCGGUGCUGUACAAUGGAAAUAUGUGAACCACAAAUGUAAUUUUAUGUUUUAUUGCCACAUUAAGAAGAGUGAAACAAAACAGGUAAGAUUAGUCUUAUAUUUCUUUGUUUAACCCAAUAUAUAAAAGUAACAUCAUUUCAACAUGUAAUCAAAACAUUAUUAAGAUUUUUUACAUUCUUUUUUUACUACGUUUUCAAAAUCCUGUUUGCAUUUUAUACCACAGCAUAUGUGAAUUCAGACUAGUCACACUUUCAGUGUUCACGAGGCACAUGUGGCCAGUGGCUGUCAUAUUGGAUGGCGUAGCUCUAUAGGAAGAUCAGCAUAAGCUCACUGUGGUGUAUUAGGUAUUCCUAAUUCCAUUAAACUAUGAACAUUGUUUAAAUUUUGGUAAAGGGUUAGGGUUGUUUUUCUAAAAAAACAUUGAAAUUAUGUAAAUACCCAAAGUCUUCAAAUAGUGUUAUGACCUCAGGCCAGACUAAACGAUGCUUCAGGGAUUGCUUAUAUAAGAAGAAAUAGUGUCUGAAAGCAAGGCAUUGGACAUGACCAACGUUUCUGUUAAUCAGUUGGACUGAAAUUCCAUUGACAUAUGUUAGGGUCAUCAGUCCACCAGGAAGUCUUCAUUGUUAGGCCAAUAAAUUUGAAGUUCGAAUAAACCCUUAGCAAGAGUUACUGAAAGAGUUCAAGUUAAAAGUUGCUUAAAGCAGUGAGUAAUGUAGAUGUUCUCAAAUUUUUGGGAAUAUAUAUUUCCCUACAUUUGAUAGCAACAGAUGCUUUCUGAAACUAAAAUCCCCUAGAUGAGAGAAUGCUGGCCUUUGCUUGCUUUCUGUUGUGCCCUGAGUGUGACAGGGUCAGCACUGUCUUAGAUUGUUCCUGGCAUUGGAAUAUUGGCAGGAAAAAGAUUUUACAUGUGAAAAAAUGCCUUGCAAUCCACAUUUUGAGAAGUGUGUGUAAUCUGCAGAGUCUUAUGGAGCAGCAGUGGUCCCCACUGUUAGACAGAUUAGGAAUCCUCCCCCUAACCUCCAUCAUAAUCUUUCUAAUUCUUAUUCUGUUAAAAUAUUUUGUGGGAAAUGAAAUUUUAAAACACAGUCUCAAAGGAUGUCUUGGAUGGUUCAAUUAUUGGCCCAUCCUCUUGUCCCAAAUUGCCAUGGAUAAUCUAUCUAGCUCUUUUUUUUUUUUAUUCUGAGCCAUAGAGCCCUUUUAUAAUGGGGUAAAUUUCUGUUUUAUUUCGUGUUUCAUUUGAUGUGACCUUUCAUUGAAAGUGGGUUUUGUUUUUAAACAGCCUAGAAUUGGAAAUGUAUGCAUAUACAUUUUUCUUUUUGCGGUUCACACAUUUUGGAGGGUGUCUAUUUCUGUCUUCUUUGGCUAGCUAUUGAGUUUGGAUAUAACUCACAGAGGUUUUCCAAAUACUAGAUUGUUUACUGUUUUCAGCUGUGAAGAUUCUACUAUAGGCCUAAAUGAUUAAAGCUUCUCCACUGAGAGCUGCACAAAAUCAGUGUUUCAUUCUAGAAAGUACUAGGUUGGUUAAAGCCUAAGAUCUAUACCUGGCAUGAUGUUAUUGAUUGUCCAUUAUCUAUCUCUGAUAUUGCGUUAGUCAUUGUGUCUCCUUAGGCAGCUUAUAUCUACAUUUGAUUUUCGUACUUUUGCCAAUGAUUGCCUUAUACACUGUGGGCUGAAAAUAAUGCUGUGACAGACCAGUAAUGGUGAAACCUUGGUUCAUUCUCAAAUAGGAAGGAAGAUUUAAAAAUAAUUUUUACCUGAAUGUUUUCUAAUUAAAAAGCAAUUCAAGCUAUUUAAAGGUAUGCUGAAAAAUACAAAGAAAAAAUGAUAAACAGACCCAAGAAUUCUACCACUCAAAUAACAAGUGUUAUUAAUAUUUUGGUAUUUAUCCUUUCAGUCUUUUUUCUAACACAUUCACUAUGUAUCCAUAUAUCUAAAUACAUGUUUGUUUAUAUUUGUGUCUGUAUAUGUACACGUACAGACUUUUAUACAGAAUUUAAGUCAUUCUGUACAUUCUGUUUUUUUGUUUCUUCUUUUUUUUUUUUUGAGACAGAAUCUCGCACUGUUGCCCGGGCUGGAGUACAGUGUCAUGAUUUUGGCUCACUGCAACCUCCGCCUCCCAGGUUCAAGAGAUUCUCCUGUCUCAGCCUCCCAAGUAGCUGGGAUUACAGGCAUGCUCUACCACUCCCAGAUUAUUAUUAUUAUUAUUAUUUUGUAUUUUUAGUGGAGACAGGGUUUCACCAUGCUGCGUAGGCUGGUCUCAAACUCCUGACCUCAGGUGAUCCUCCCACCUCGGCCUCCCAAAGUGCUGGGAUUGCAGGUGUGAGCCACUGUGCCCAGCCUGUACAUUCUGUUUUAUACUUUAAAAAACCAAGUUAAGAUUGCAUUUUUGACCAUGGGAAUUUAACUGCAAAAAUAAAACAAUAUUUAAGAAAAAAUAUUAAAGUGAAGAAGAAAGCCAUCCUUAAUCCAGCCACUGUUAAGAGAAAAAUUAUAUUUAUUUUUGUCUAUUCUUAAUUUUUCUCAACAGGCCUAUUUAUUUAAUUUUUUACAGGCAGGUGAAUUUGAAUUGUUCACAGUGAAGACUGGUAAUUAGAGAGGGAAAAGAUAGGGUCUGAAAAUUCUCACACUUAUGAGAUACAGCAUUCAGAUGAUACUUUUCACCGUUGAAAUUUAAAGUUAGAAGUGUUCUUCAGUUGGUUAGAGUAUUUUAAUGAUGACUAUGAUUUUAAUUCAGAAGUGGAAGAAACUUUAAGAAUGAACCUAAUGACUACUCUUUUCUCAGUUGGCUCUCAGAGCUUUGCAUGCCAUUCCAAAGUGCAAGGUAUAAUUCAUGAACAUAAAAAGUUUCUCUGGGAAUGUAUAGAAACUGCAUCUUCUACAUCUUUUGUGCUGAUUCCUCUUUCACUUGAAUUGGCUGGGUUGUCAGGGAAACAGUUAACAUACAGUUUUCUGGAAACAGUUAAUAUACAGAAUAAAAUAUAUGGCAUAGCUCUUUUAGCAUAUGGAUUAAAUUGAUACAAUAAGGGAAUGUUUUAAAUUUUGUGUAAAAUAUUUUUGCACAAGAAUCAGGCUACCUGAAUAAUUGUUUAUCUUUCAGGUGACCGAAAAGCACAGCAGCCCUCUUAGUUGCAAAUGUGUUGAGUUGUGUUAAAAAAAAAAAAAAAAGAUGGAGAGGAAUGCCCUGAUUCUUUACAGAUUUGAAGAAUUAUAUCUCAAUUAAUUUUAUAAUUUGAACUUGGUAUUUUCUUGCUCAAAUUCCAAAGGGGAAGAAACCCCAUUGUUUAUCAAGGUAAUGUUUAAAGAUGUUUCAUACUAUGUUAUAAAUAUGAAGAACAUAGUCCUUGUGUUUUUAGAGUUGGCUCCAUAAAGCAUCAGAUGUUAUAAUAGAAAAGCAUUUCAAAAUGAAAAGGAUAUUUAAACAGAAGUUUCCAUGUGCCCCAGGAAGAAUUUAAAGUCAAGCUACCCCCCUCCCAUUUAAUUCAGUCAUUAACUGGACUUGCUCUGUAGUUUGGGGGGAUUGUAAUAGUUUACACCUGUUUCAACUUUUGCUGUUUUUAUUGGCAGUGGCUUUUGCCAUCCCAUAUUUCUUGUGAAGCAAAAAUAUGAAAUAAAAUAUGGCAAAGCAUUGGAGAAAUUAUAAUAAACAUAAAAAAUGAAUCGUUCAGCUUAAAAUAUGAAAUGCUUUACCUGCACAUUCAGCCAGCCACGUUUCAGUAGUAUUGAAGUAAUUUAUUCCCGGAGUUGUGUGUCAUGAAAAUAAAGACAAUUGCUUUCAUUGGCAGGAAUAAUCCAGGGUUUUUACAUCCAAGCGAAUAAACUUUGGAACAUCAGGCAGACGUUAUAUUGUAAAGACAGUUUAAGGAAAACCUGCUAAAUCAUUAUAUCUGUGCUCAUGUCACUGUGGAAUAAAAAAGAUGAAGGAGUAUCAGUGUCUAAGAUUGCAAAGACUCAAUAGAAGUAUUUUACCACAGAGUGUAAUCAAACUUUAAAGGUCAAGCAAUAUCAUGACAUAAAGUAUGGUUUGGCUCAUUUCACAGGCUCCAUUUUGCCCUCCAAAUAUAAUGAAAAGGAAAUGAUUUGAGUCAAUAUAUUAUCAUAUCUCAUAUAUAUUUUUUUCUUCCGAUCCAGCUCUCUAAUGGUCUCCAUAUAAGUGCCCUUUGUUCUUCAGAUCUAACGGUAGCUGUCCAGCUCCAGUGUUGGGUUCGGAGUGAAAUAAUUAAGUUUUUAGUGCAUUGUCUAGAAUGAGAAUUGCUAAAUUAAAUUUAUAAGUUUAAUUUGGUUAGAAUUGUGACUGUGAAAAACUCUCUGGGAAAGUUGCUAGGAGAACUGAAUUUUAACUUUGGCUUAAUCUCACCAGUUAGGUUGCUUUGAAUAUUUUACAGGUUGGGGUUGUAAUUUGAAUGAAGGUAGGGCCUUGCCUAUUUUGAUUCAUUAGCAUCGAACCUAAGUCCUAAGUAUUUGCAGAAUGAAAGUGUCAGCUUUUCUGGGUCUGUAAAAUGAGCAUUUUAUUUUAUUUAUCUUAUUUUUUUUAAAUGAGCAUUUUAAAUGCCUAAUUUUAUAUUGAGAAAAAUGUUCUUCAGUGAUACCCUUUUCCCCAAUCUCUCACUUCUUGGAAAGACUUUAUAUUUUGAUACUAAUGAAUGCAGACUAAGUGGGAGAAGUAGACUCUCAAAUUUGGGCUCAGAAGAAUCCGUGUUUGGGGGAAGAGAAGAAGACUUUUAGUGAAAUGUCACUCUCUUAAUAGGCUCUCAUGGCCUUUGUUAGCUUUGUCUGCUUGGGGUCAGUGAAAGUCCUUCAGGUGACCUGGCAUCCUGGGAGUGAAUUGAGUAUGCUUCUCCCUAGGAAGGGCUAAUGAUUGGGACUCAACACCGUUUGCACCUGAGACCAUGAUCUAACCAACAACUCAUCAGCAUCUUUUACCAAGAUUUAGAAGUGACAAUGCUCCCCUUGCCUAGAUUUAAGAUGGUGCGGCUGAGACCACCUUCCUGGCAGCCAGCUGCUGCUGAAGGGAAAGGCAGAAGUGGGGAAGACUUUUUUCAAAAGAUCAUGGAGGAAACAAAUACGCAGAUUGCUUGGCCAUCAAAACUGAAGAUCGGAGCCAAAUCCAAGAAAGAUCCCCAUAUUAAGGUUUCUGGAAAGAAAGAAGAUGUUAAAGAAGCCAAGGAAAUGAUCAUGUCUGUCUUAGACACAAAAAGCAAUCGAGUCACACUGAAGAUGGAUGUUUCACAUACAGAACAUUCACAUGUAAUCGGCAAAGGUGGCAACAAUAUUAAAAAAGUGAUGGAAGAAACCGGAUGCCAUAUCCACUUUCCAGAUUCCAACAGGAAUAACCAAGCAGAAAAAAGCAACCAGGUAUCUAUAGCGGGACAACCAGCAGGAGUAGAAUCUGCCCGAGUUAGAAUUCGGGAGCUGCUUCCUUUGGUGCUGAUGUUUGAGCUACCAAUUGCUGGAAUUCUUCAACCGGUUCCUGAUCCUAAUUCCCCCUCUAUUCAGCAUAUAUCACAAACGUACAAUAUUUCAGUAUCAUUUAAACAGCGUUCCCGAAUGUAUGGUGCUACUGUCAUAGUACGAGGGUCUCAGAAUAACACUAGUGCUGUGAAGGAAGGAACUGCCAUGCUGUUAGAACAUCUUGCUGGGAGCUUAGCAUCAGCUAUUCCUGUGAGCACACAACUAGAUAUUGCAGCUCAACAUCAUCUCUUUAUGAUGGGUCGAAAUGGGAGCAACAUCAAACAUAUCAUGCAGAGAACAGGUGCUCAGAUCCACUUUCCUGAUCCCAGUAAUCCACAAAAGAAAUCUACCGUCUACCUCCAGGGCACCAUUGAGUCUGUCUGUCUUGCAAGGCAAUAUCUCAUGGGUUGUCUUCCUCUUGUGUUGAUGUUUGAUAUGAAGGAAGAAAUUGAAGUAGAUCCACAAUUCAUUGCGCAGUUGAUGGAACAGCUUGAUGUCUUCAUCAGUAUUAAACCAAAGCCCAAACAGCCAAGCAAGUCUGUGAUUGUGAAAAGUGUUGAGCGAAAUGCCUUAAAUAUGUAUGAAGCAAGGAAAUGUCUCCUCGGACUUGAAAGCAGUGGGGUUACCAUAGCAACCAGUCCAUCCCCAGCAUCCUGCCCUGCCGGCCUGGCAUGUCCCAGCCUGGAUAUCUUAGCUUCAGCAGGCCUUGGACUCACUGGACUAGGUCUUUUGGGACCCACCACCUUAUCUCUGAACACUUCAACAACCCCAAACUCACUCUUGAAUGCUCUUAAUAGCUCAGUCAGUCCUUUGCAAAGUCCAAGUUCUGGUACACCCAGCCCCACAUUAUGGGCACCCCCACUUGCUAAUACUUCAAGUGCCACAGGUUUUUCUGCUAUACCACACCUUAUGAUUCCAUCUACUGCCCAAGCCACAUUAACUAAUAUUUUGUUGUCUGGAGUGCCCACCUAUGGGCACACAGCUCCAUCUCCCCCUCCUGGCUUGACUCCUGUUGAUGUCCAUAUCAACAGUAUGCAGACCGAAGGCAAAAAAAUCUCUGCUGCUUUAAAUGGACAUGCACAGUCUCCAGAUAUAAAAUAUGGUGCAAUAUCCACUUCAUCACUUGGAGAAAAAGUGCUGAGUGCAAAUCACGGGGAUCCGUCCAUCCAGACAAGUGGGUCUGAGCAGACAUCUCCCAAAUCAAGCCCCACUGAAGGUUGUAAUGAUGCUUUUGUUGAAGUAGGCAUGCCUCGAAGUCCUUCCCAUUCUGGGAAUGCUGGUGACUUGAAACAGAUGAUGUGUCCCUCCAAGGUUUCCUGUGCCAAAAGGCAGACAGUGGAACUAUUGCAAGGCACGAAAAACUCACACUUACACAGCACUGACAGGUUGCUCUCAGACCCUGAACUGAGUGCUACCGAAAGCCCUUUGGCUGACAAGAAGGCUCCAGGGAGUGAGCGCGCUGCAGAGAGGGCAGCAGCUGCCCAGCAAAACUCCGAAAGGGCCCACCUUGCUCCACGGUCAUCAUAUGUCAACAUGCAGGCAUUUGACUAUGAACAGAAGAAGCUAUUAGCCACCAAAGCUAUGUUAAAGAAACCAGUGGUGACGGAGGUCAGAACGCCCACAAAUACCUGGAGUGGCCUGGGUUUUUCUAAAUCCAUGCCAGCUGAAACUAUCAAGGAGUUGAGAAGGGCCAAUCAUGUGUCCUAUAAGCCCACAAUGACAACCACUUAUGAGGGCUCAUCCAUGUCCCUUUCACGGUCCAACAGUCGUGAGCACUUGGGAGGUGGAAGCGAAUCUGAUAACUGGAGAGACCGAAAUGGAAUUGGACCUGGAAGUCAUAGUGAAUUUGCAGCUUCUAUUGGCAGCCCUAAGCGUAAACAAAACAAAUCAACGGAACACUAUCUCAGCAGUAGCAAUUACAUGGACUGCAUUUCCUCGCUGACAGGAAGCAAUGGCUGUAACUUAAAUAGCUCUUUCAAAGGUUCUGACCUCCCUGAGCUCUUCAGCAAACUGGGCCUGGGCAAAUACACAGAUGUUUUCCAGCAACAAGAGAUCGAUCUUCAGACAUUCCUCACUCUCACAGAUCAGGAUCUGAAGGAGCUGGGAAUAACUACUUUUGGUGCCAGGAGGAAAAUGCUGCUUGCAAUUUCAGAACUAAAUAAAAACCGAAGAAAGCUUUUUGAAUCGCCAAAUGCACGCACCUCUUUCCUGGAAGGUGGAGCGAGUGGAAGGCUACCCCGUCAGUAUCACUCAGACAUUGCUAGUGUCAGUGGCCGCUGGUAGCAGCACCCUCUUGGCACAUGCCCGCUGACUAACUGUAAAGUGGACACAGGAGAUGUAUGAACAGCCUUCACAGCACACCAUCCUUAGCACUCUGGGUGUCUGGUAUCAGGACCAAAGCAUUUUAUUCGCACCUGUACUUUAUGGCAAAAAGGAAGAAGAGAGAGAAGAUGUUCUUAUGAUGUCAUACAGAACACCAAAUAUGGAUUACUUUUUUAAAAUGGCAGUUGGACAGAAUUUGCAAUAUAAGGAUAGGGCUUUAUUUCCUGUUUUUAUUUACCUAUAUAACAUAUGCACUGAUGAUUUUUUUUUUUUUUUUUUUUUUUUUUUUUUUACUUAAAAUGAAGGAUGAAUUGACAUCUGGGAUGCCAGAAGACUUAGAAGUUAUUUUGUUUGCUUGUUUUGUUUGGGUAUUUGGGGAUUUUUAAAAAAUAAUCAAAGUGGAAUUUUCUGGUACUGCUUUAAAAUAAUUAUUGUGGUCUUUCAGCACUUUACACGUUCUAAUUUCUUGUCCUAUGGAAGUUCUCGCUGUCUCCAUCUCUCUCAUUUUUGUGUCACCUAAUAUGUUGGUACAGAUAAGAGUUAGUCACAUUUUUCUGACUGCAUCAAACUUUUAUUUGAAAUGGUACUGGAUCUUAGUUUCUGUGCAGAAUAUUCUGUGAUUUUGGGAAAUGUAAGUGAGUCCACUUGCUUCUGGACCAAUUCUGUUUCAUGUAUGUUAGCAUCCUAGAAACACCUAGCAAUGGACCUAGUUCACAGUAAUAGGUGCAAAGAAAGACCAAAUGGACUUUGCAGUAUUAACCCUUUGCAGUCGUCAUACUUAGCUGCUGCCUGUAAUGCUAAAAUGAUUUUAAUGGUUGUCUGGAGGCAAAGGGCUGUUUUUUAGUAUAUUGCCACUAAAGGACAUUUAUUUAUAUCAAACUUUUAUUUUUAGAUAUUAUAAGCAUACAGUACAUAAUUGAUGAAAUUGAUAUUUACUAGAGAUUUAUGGUAGAGAAUGGACGACAUUCAAUAACUGGAGCCCGAGAUUGUCACUUUAUUUAAAAAGACAAAUAAUCAUCUGACAAGACAGCACUGUUGCCAUUAUAAGGAGAAAUAGAUUACAAUCCUUAUCAUGUACACGUUAGCUAUGUUCCGUAUGGCCACAGGACUUUCCUGAAACCGUAUCUGUCUGCUUGAAGUAGACUUAUGUUUGUUGAGAAUGAACAGGCUUAUUUGAGCCUCCAGGGUGGCAGUUCAUAAAGACAGCUAAGUUCUGAAGGAAAAAAAAAAUAUAUCUUUUUAAGUGGCUAGAGUCAUUAUUACAAUCUUAUACUGUGAAAGUCCAAGAAAUCAGGCAACAUUGUUUCCUGGGUCUUUUCAGAGAUCUUAUAGAUUUAUGAAGUGUUUUUAAUCCAUGAAGAAACACUAAAGUGCCUUUCUUUCUUCAAAGCAAUAUUAUUUCCAAGUAUAUUAAUUUGUUAGAAAACUUUCCCAUAGGAAAUGUUGUCAAGUUACCUGUACUGUAAAGAGUUAUUUAUGUUCAGUAGUCAAGAUUUUCUACAUGGACAUAAACCACUCUCACGUGCUCUCAGCAGAAGGCAUUAGAUAAGCAUAUACAAGAAUUGGGUACUUUUAUACAAAUAUGGGAUAAGAAAUACUUGCCUGACACUUUUCCAUGGCUGAGUCUGACCAUUACAGUAAGAACAAGAAUUGAAGAGGCAUUUUGCACACAGAAACAUUCUCACUUUAAAAAAUGGUAUUGGUUACCUUGAAGGCAUAGAUAAUGGGCCUGUCAUAAAAUUAUCAAUUAUAACUGGCACCGAGGGACUGCCCUUUUUAAGCUAAACUAAGCCUUAUCUGCUUAAGGAUGUUGAACUGAAUCACUCCCUUUACUCAUCCUGUGCAUAUGUGUACAAAUGGUCAUGUGGAUCAUGUGAUGAUCAUCCAUCUUAUUUGAUUGUAUUAAUGCAUCAUGCUAAACAUGUAGUACAGGUUAACAAUACCAGAUUUAUGUCCUGUUCAACAACUCAGUACUCUAAAUGUUGUUAUGCUUUUAAUAAGACCUUCCCAGAUAAUAAUCUUGGAGCUCUUUUCCCAGCUGUCUACCAUGCAUUUGCAACAGGAGGAAGAUGUAAUGAAUAUGCAGUAUUAAGUUGAUUUAUGAACAGUGCUUUGAUAUGCCAAAGGGAAAACUGUCCCACUUAAAUUAGAUUAAGUAGGGUGGCUAAAAAUAAAUAAAAACACUGGAAAUUCUUUCUCUCACUUUCUCUUGAUGCAAUGAAGGGAAUAUGACACUACAGUAUACAGAGUUGUUGUUAUAUGAUGCACAAAAUAUUUUGAUGAUUUGAAUAAAUGUUAACUUUUAAUCUGCGCCUUAAUAAUGACUGGUUAUCUGUAAAUAUAGAACAGAUACAGAUUGUAUUUUUCUGUGGGUUUUUGUCCUUUUAGUGAUUUUUUUCCAAAAACGAGAGAUGGAAUUAACAUUGAAAAUGGGAAAUUUUUCUAACUGAAUCAAUUGUUACAUGAAAAAUAAAUUUAUAUAACCCCUUUGUAUUGCUCUUGCUA